GCGUCUGCCAGGAGCUACGGCCGGAAGAUGGCGGCGGCCGCAGAGUUGUCGCUACUGGAGAAGUCCCUGGGACUGAGUAAGGGGAAUAAAUACAGUGCUCAGGGCGAGCGACAGAUUCCAGUUCUUCAGACAAACAAUGGUCCAAGUCUAACAGGAUUGACUACUAUAGCAGCUCAUCUAGUCAAGCAAGCCAACAAAGAAUAUUUGCUGGGGAGUACUGCAGAAGAAAAAGCAAUCGUUCAGCAGUGGUUAGAAUACAGGGUCACUCAAGUAGAUGGGCACUCCAGUAAAAAUGACAUCCACACACUGUUGAAGGAUCUUAAUUCAUAUCUUGAAGAUAAAGUCUACCUUACAGGGUAUAACUUUACAUUAGCAGAUAUACUAUUGUACUAUGGACUUCAUCGCUUUAUAGUUGACCUGACAGUUCAAGAAAAGGAGAAAUAUCUUAAUGUGUCUCGCUGGUUUUGUCACAUUCAGCAUUAUCCAGGCAUCAGGCAACAUCUGUCUAGUGUUGUCUUCAUCAAGAACAGACUAUAUACUAAUUCCCACUAGAAGCUGUCCAUGCCAUACAGAAGAUCUAUUAAAAAUGUUUUAAAUGGAAAAUGUACUCUAGACCACAGGACUAAUGUAAAUUAAUAUACAGUCAUUCAUUAUUUGUUGAAGUUGAUAGAAUUUUUGAAGUGUAAACUUGUGUCUGAAUGUUUUAUUUGUUCUUUAGCUGAAGUUUUGCAAUUUUUAUGUCAAAAUUCAAUUGCUAUUAAACAAGUUGAGAUCCAGUUAUAAAUUAACCUUGUUUUUAGUAGAUGACAUUUAUUUCAAUAAAAGUUGCAAAUCGGGCUUAAUCUUAAAAUUGGUGGUCAUUUCAAUGGUUGACAUAUUUGGCUAUUUAUUAACCUCUCUUUCAUAUUCUAAAAUUCAUUUUCCCCUUAUGGAUAUUUAUGGUAGUUUGUUAAGAACUGAUAAAUUGUGCCAAGGAAGCCAAAAGGGAAGACAGAUGGAUUUGUUUUAAAAUAUUUAUGUGAGCUAGUAAAUGUGGUUGAAAAAAUA